GCGGCGCCUGCUUGGCGCGACGCUCUAGCGGUUACCGCUGCGGGCUGGCUGGGCGUAGUGGGGCUGCGCGGCUGCCACGGAGCUAGAGGGCAAGUGUGCUCGGCCCAGCGUGCAGGGAACGCGGGCGGCCAGACAACGGGCUGGGCUCCGGGGCCUGCGGCGCGGGCGCUGAGCUGGCAGGGCGGGUCGGGGCGCGGGCUGCAUCCGCAUCUCCUCCAUCGCCUGCAGUAAGGGCGGCCGCGGCGAGCCUUUGAGGGGAACGACUUGUCGGAGCCCUAACCAGGGGUAUCUCUGAGCCUGGUGGGAUCCCCGGAGCGUCACAUCACUUUCCGAUCACUUCAAAGUACAGCAGACCGAGGACACGGUUGUUACCAAGACCAGGCUGUUGCCUUGGAAGAGCCCAGAGCGUGUCAAGGGAGACAGCCACAUCACGCCAGAAAUACAUGACAGCUGGAUUAGCCCUGGGAGAGGGAGGCCCAGAUGUGGGAGCUCAGGGGAGGUGCAGCUCAACGUGGAGUUUGGAGGAGGCUACCUUGACCUUUGAAUGCCAAGUGGGAGCCAGCCAGAUGAAAGGAUCCAGCGUCUGUGUGCAAUUUCGUUUUGAGAAUUCCUUCUAACCAGAUCAGGAAAGCUCUCUUACCAGGAAUAGCCCCAGGAAAGACAAUAUGGAUUAGACGUACUCCAUGAUAACUGGCGUUUUGCAUCCAAGUGUGCCUCUUGAUCCCGUAACUGCUAACUGGAAGUCAAGAAACUAAAAACAUUAUCUCUUGUACCAUUAAUUAAGUGGGAUUUAUUUGAGUGCAAGAUCGUUUUCUCAGUGGUGGUGGAAGUUGCCUCAUCGCAGGCAGAUGUUGGGGCUUUGUCCGAACAGCUCCCCUCUGCCAGCUUCUGUAGAUAAGGGUUAAAAACUAAUAUUUAUAUGACAGAAGAAAAAGAUGUCAUUCCGUAAAGUAAACAUCAUCAUCUUGGUCCUGGCUGUUGCUCUCUUCUUACUGGUUUUGCACCAUAACUUCCUCAGCUUGAGCAGUUUGUUAAGGAAUGAGGUUACAGAUUCAGGAAUUGUAGGGCCUCAACCUAUAGACUUUGUCCCAAAUGCUCUCCGACAUGCAGUAGAUGGGAGACAAGAGGAGAUUCCUGUGGUCAUCGCUGCAUCUGAAGACAGGCUUGGGGGGGCCAUUGCAGCUAUAAACAGCAUUCAGCACAACACUCGCUCCAAUGUGAUUUUCUACAUUGUUACUCUCAACAAUACAGCAGACCAUCUCCGGUCCUGGCUCAACAGUGAUUCCCUGAAAAGCAUCAGAUACAAAAUUGUCAAUUUUGACCCUAAACUUUUGGAAGGAAAAGUAAAGGAGGAUCCUGACCAGGGGGAAUCCAUGAAACCUUUAACCUUUGCAAGGUUCUACUUGCCAAUUCUGGUUCCCAGCGCAAAGAAGGCCAUAUACAUGGAUGAUGAUGUAAUUGUGCAAGGUGAUAUUCUUGCCCUUUACAAUACAGCACUGAAGCCAGGACAUGCAGCUGCAUUUUCAGAAGAUUGUGAUUCAGCCUCUACUAAAGUUGUCAUCCGUGGAGCAGGAAACCAGUACAAUUACAUUGGCUAUCUUGACUAUAAAAAGGAAAGAAUUCGUAAGCUUUCCAUGAAAGCCAGCACUUGCUCAUUUAAUCCUGGAGUUUUUGUUGCAAACCUGACGGAAUGGAAACGACAGAAUAUAACUAACCAACUGGAAAAAUGGAUGAAACUCAAUGUAGAAGAGGGACUGUAUAGCAGAACCCUGGCUGGUAGCAUCACAACACCUCCUCUGCUUAUCGUAUUUUAUCAACAGCACUCUACCAUCGAUCCUAUGUGGAAUGUCCGCCACCUUGGUUCCAGUGCUGGAAAACGAUAUUCACCUCAGUUUGUAAAGGCUGCCAAGUUACUCCAUUGGAAUGGACAUUUGAAGCCAUGGGGAAGGACUGCUUCAUAUACUGAUGUUUGGGAAAAAUGGUAUAUUCCAGACCCAACAGGCAAAUUCAACCUAAUCCGAAGAUAUACCGAGAUCUCAAACAUAAAGUGAAACAGAAUUUGAACUGUAAGCAAGCAUUUCUCAGGAAGUCCUGGAAGAUAGCAUGCGUGGGAAGUAACAGUUGCUAGGCUUCAAUGCCUAUCGGUAGCAAGCCAUGGAAAAAGAUGUGUCAGCUAGGUAAAGAUGACAAACUGCCCUGUCUGGCAGUCAGCUUCCCAGACAGACUAUAGACUAUAAAUAUGUCUCCAUCUGCCUUACCAAGUGUUUUCUUACUACAAUGCUGAAUGACUGGAAAGAAGAACUGAUAUGGCUAGUUCAGCUAGCUGGUACAGAUAAUUCAAAACUGCUGUUGGUUUUAAUUUUGUAACCUGUGGCCUGAUCUGUAAAUAAAACUUACAUUUUUCAAUAGG